GCGAGACUUCGGCGGCGCAGCAAUGGCCAGAGCGUGAGUGCCGCUGACAGAAGUCAAGAGAAUCGGCUGGGACGGGGUUGGGGCGACAACGGGCCGGGGGGGACCCGACAGGCCAGAGCCCCUUGGGGAGGAGCGGCGGCUGGAGGCGCGAGGCUCCUCCGGAUGCCCGGAGAGCCGCUUGCGACUUAACUCCCGCCUCUUUCCCAGAUGCCGCGUCACUGCUCCGCCGCCGGCUGCUGCACACGGGACACGCGCGAGACGCGCAACCGCGGCAUCUCCUUCCACAGACUUCCCAAGAAGGACAACCCGAGGCGAGGCUUGUGGCUGGCCAACUGCCAGCGGCUGGACCCCAGCGGCCAGGGCCUGUGGGACCCGGCAUCCGAGUACAUCUACUUCUGCUCCAAACACUUUGAGGAGGACUGCUUUGAGCUGGUGGGAAUCAGUGGAUAUCACAGGCUAAAGGAGGGGGCAGUCCCCACCAUAUUUGAGUCUUUCUCCAAGUUGCGCCGGACAACCAAGACCAAAGGACACAGUUACCCACCUGGCCCCGCUGAAGUCAGCCGGCUCAGACGAUGCAGGAAGCGCUGCUCCGAGGGCCGAGGGCCCACAACUCCAUUUUCUCCACCUCCACCUGCUGAUGUCACCUGCUUUCCUGUGGAAGAGGCCUCAGCACCUGCCACUUUGCCGGCCUCCCCAGCUGGGAGGCUGGAGCCUGGCCUUAGCAGCCCCUUUUCAGACCUACUGGGCCCCUUGGGUGCCCAGGCAGAUGAAGCAGGCUGCAGCGCCCAGCCUUCACCAGAGCGGCAGCCCUCCCCUCUCGAACCACGGCCAGUCUCCCCCUCAGCGUAUAUGCUGCGCCUGCCCCCACCCGCCGGAGCCUACAUCCAGAAUGAACACAGCUACCAGGUGGGCAGCGCCUUACUCUGGAAGCGGCGAGCCGAGGCAGCCCUUGAUGCCCUUGACAAGGCCCAGCGCCAGCUGCAGGCCUGCAAGCGGCGGGAGCAGCGGCUGCGGUUGAGACUGACCAAGCUGCAGCAGGAGCGGGCACGGGAGAAGCGGGCACAGGCAGAUGCCCGCCAGACUCUGAAGGAGCAUGUGCAGGACUUUGCCAUGCAGCUGAGCAGCAGCAUGGCCUGAGGGGCUGCUGGACUGACCGAGGGGCUGCCCAGCAAGACUGCAGCCUCUUCCUCCCUCAGAUCCCACCAGACCCACCAGGUGCCAUAAUAAAGCGGAUUCUAGACGGAGGGCCUGCUGUCUGGCUCAGCUGGGGGCUGGAGCCCCUCUGAGUACUAAGCUUGCUGCCCCAGACAGUGGCUGCAGCUCCUAGAGGGCUCAGUCCAAGCUCUUUGCCAAGGAGAACAGGGAGCCUGGCUCUCACCCCUCAGAGCUACUGGUAGACAGGUGGCAGUCAGCCCUGCUAGCGCAGCUCCGUGCCCCACAGGGUUCUCUGAAGGGGCAGGAUGGUGUGAGUAGGGGCCAGGAAGACAGCUCCAGGCGCCCUUUCCAUAGGAUCUGAAACAGCCCUGACUUAAACCAGCCAGCCCCUUUGAGAACACUUCUAAAACCCAGUCUAGAUCCGGUUCUCAAGCAGGAGCAUGACAGGCUUCUGUCCACAGGCCCCAUCAGCCUGGUGGGUAAGCUGGACAACCCUCUCCCCGCCCCCUUCACUACCAUCUCUAUUUGAAAAACGGGGAUGAUGAUGACAAUCAUCAACCUCCUGGGUCAUGUCAGCAGGUAGUAAAGCCCCAACAAGCUAGUCCCUGGAAAUCUAGGAAGAGGUGGCCAGAACAUGGAGACAAGCACUCAGGUCCUGGCCUCAGCAUCCUUUUCCUUCAACUCCCAGGAACCUGGAAGGCCUUGCUGCAGCUGCAGUUCUCAAACAGCUCCGUCUUGGGGUGACUCACUGCAAGUAU